CAGGAAUUCAUUGAAGAGUUGCUGUCUCCCCCUUUUGGGGGUUUAGUGGCAUUUGUGAAGGAGGCUGAGGCUUUGAUUGAGCGUGGACAGGCUGAGCGACUUCGAGGGGAAGAAGCCCGGGUAACUCAGCUGAUCCGUGGCUUUGGUAGUUCCUGGAAAUCAUCAGUGGAAUCUCUGAGUCAGGAUGUAAUGCGGAGUUUCACCAACUUCAGAAAUGGCACCAGUAUCAUUCAGGGAGCGCUGACCCAGCUGAUCCAGCUCUAUCAUCGCUUCCACCGGGUGCUGUCCCAGCCGCAGCUCCGAGCCCUCCCUGCCCGGGCUGAGCUCAUCAACAUUCACCACCUUAUGGUGGAGCUCAAGAAGCAUAAGCCCAACUUCUGAUGUGCCAGAAACCGCCCUGAGAUCUGCCGGUCAUCUCCAUGGACUUCUGCACCCCAUUCCAUACCCUUCUUCACCUGGGGUACCCCUUCCAGUUUUCCCCUUGCUUCCCAGGCCCUUGACAUGGCUUACCUGCCUUCACUCCCAGCACCUUGCCCAACAGGAUAAGCUGGAUCCCCUUGGCCUUCUGAAUAUCCCAGUGUCUUCAGGUUUCCCAAGACCACUUCCCUGUGGGCUUCCAAAAUGGCCUUUAUCAUUUCUCCAGUCUGUCACCCUCCUUUCCUGCUCCCAUACACCCAAGGCUUGUUUCUUCCCCUGUAAAAACCACUGCCUCAAUCUCUGGUUCACUCAACUAGUCACCAUGUCCUGAGGCAUGAAGCCUCCUCAGCUCUUGGAAUUGCUGGCAAGGGGUGACUGCCUCUGAGUCAUUGUGUUUUUCAAAGUGAUUUCUUUUCUGUAGCUUUUUGACCUAAGAUCUCAGCAAUUUGAACACUAACCUCUCCCCUCCUGGCUCAAGAAUUACUCCGAAGUCAGUCUGCAGAAAAUAAAUAUUUAGUAUGACAUGACACUUA